ACAGUUCUGCAGCCACUCGGUACGGCGCUAACGCCGCGAGGUAGCUCGGUGCGUCUCGCAGUACCAGUGCGAACCUUUGGGCUCUCCAGGUCCGAGAUCCUAGUCUCCUGUCGGCUCUGAGGAGGAUGGAUCCUUCUGCGGAUACAUGGGACCUCUCCUCACCUUUAAUAUCAUUAUGGAUAAACAGGUUUUACAUUUAUCUGGGCUUUGCUGUUAGCAUUAGCCUUUGGAUUUGUGUCCAGAUUGUCAUCGAGAUGCAGGGAUUUGCAACAGUUCUUGCUGAAGCAGUUACGUCCCUGGAUCUGCCUGUGGCCAUUAUUAAUCUAAAAGAAUAUGAUCCAGAUGAUCAUCUGAUAGAAGAGGUGACUAGUAAAAAUGUCUGUGUCUUCCUGGUUGCGACAUACACUGACGGCCUACCAACCGAAAGUGCAGAGUGGUUCUGCAAAUGGUUAGAGGAAGCAUCCAUUGAUUUUCGAUUUGGCAAAACUUACCUGAAGGGUAUGAGAGAUGCGGUAUUUGGCCUGGGAAAUUCUGCCUAUGCUAGCCACUUCAACAAGGUUGGCAAAAAUGUUGACAAGUGGCUCUGGAUGCUUGGCGUGCAUCGUGUGAUGAGUCGAGGGGAGGGCGACUGCGACGUGGUUAAAAGCAAGCACGGCAGCAUUGAGGCCAACUUCAGAGCAUGGAAGACCAAGUUCAUCUCCCAGCUGCAGGCACUUCAGAAAGGGGAGAGAAAGAAGUCCUGUGGCGGCCACUGCAAGAAAGGCAAAUGUGAAUCUCACCAACAUGGCUCAGAGGAGAGGGAGGAAGGAUCUCAAGAGCAGGACGAAUUGCAUCACAGAGACACCAAGGAGGAAGAACCCUUCGAGAGCUCCAGUGAAGAAGAGUUUGGUGGUGAGGACCAUCAGAGCCUAAAUUCCAUUGUUGAUGUUGAAGAUUUGGGCAAAAUUAUGGAUCACGUGAAGAAAGAAAAGAGAGAAAAGGAACAGCAGGAAGAGAAGUCUGGUUUGUUCAGGAACAUGGGGAGGAAUGAAGAUGGUGAAAGAAGAGCUAUGAUAACUCCUGCUCUCCGAGAAGCCCUUACUAAACAAGUCGAUGCUCCGAGGGAGAGGAGCUUGUUACAAACACACAUUCUAUGGAAUGAGAGCCAUCGCUGCAUGGAAACCACCCCGAGCUUGGCGUGUGCUAAUAAAUGUGUCUUCUGUUGGUGGCACCACAACAACCCUGUGGGCACUGAAUGGUUGUGGAAGAUGGACCAGCCUGAAAUGAUCUUGAAGGAAGCCAUUGAAAACCAUCAGAACAUGAUUAAGCAGUUUAAAGGAGUACCGGGCGUCAAAGCAGAACGCUUUGAAGAAGGAAUGACGGUAAAGCACUGUGCAUUGUCCCUCGUGGGAGAACCAAUAAUGUACCCAGAGAUCAACAGGUUUUUGAAGCUACUCCACCAGUGUAAAAUCUCCAGCUUCCUGGUCACAAAUGCACAAUUUCCUGCGGAAAUCAGGAACCUCGAGCCAGUUACUCAGCUGUAUGUCAGUGUGGAUGCCAGUACCAAAGACAGCCUGAAGAAAAUCGACCGCCCACUCUUCAAGGAUUUCUGGCAGCAAUUCCUUGACAGUUUAAAAGCCUUGGCAGUCAAGCAACAACGAACUGUCUACAGACUGAUGCUCGUGAAAGCAUGGAACGUGGACGAGCUCCAGGCCUACGCGCAGCUCGUGUCCCUGGGGAAUCCUGACUUCAUCGAAGUGAAGGGCGUUACCUACUGCAGAGAAAGUUCAGCAAGCAGUCUUACCAUGGCCCAUGUGCCCUGGCAUGAGGAAGUGGUACAGUUUGUCCGCGAGCUGGUGGAUCUGAUCCCCGAAUAUGAAAUUGCAUGUGAACACGAACACUCUAAUUGCCUCCUGAUAGCACACAGAAAGUUUAAAAUUGGUGGUGAAUGGUGGACAUGGAUCGAUUAUAACCGCUUCCAGGAGCUCAUCCAGGAAUAUGAAGAUAGUGGUGGAUCAAAAACGUUCAGCGCAAAGGAUUAUAUGGCCAGAACUCCUCACUGGGCAUUAUUUGGUGCCAAUGAAAGAAGCUUUGAUCCCAAGGACACAAGACAUCAGAGAAAGAACAAAUCAAAGGCUAUUUCUGGAUGUUGAGAUUAUCUGAUUUCAAGGUACUGAAGGACAAAAACUUGGAUGGCCUCAAAAGGUUCUUGAACACCACUCUGAUUCUCCAAGGACGAAUUACGUAAAUUAUACUUUCAUACAAAGGAGACGAUAAGGCAGUAAACAUGGAGACACGGGGGACAGCGUCCACACUCAGAGGGCCUGGGCCACAGCCCCGAUGUUUCUUUUCAGAACUCAGCCCCUUUCCUGAUUUUACUUCUAAGAGGAAAAUUAUUUUGGGGAGGAACUACACAGUCGUGAUUAGAAUUUAACUGAUGGUUUUGUAUUAUAACUUCUAAGACCUGCCAGAAUGCUAGUCCUGAGAGUGUCAGACAAGGAAGAAAUCCCUGGGCCUCUUCCCCUCACCUGGCCCUUGGAUUUCAUGGAGCAGCCACUUAGCAUUGAAUUGCACUACCCUGAGCUAAACGUGUCUGUGCUUUCUAAGAUAAGAGCUUGAUCCCUUUCUUCUGUCUUAAGACAGCACCUCCUGAAAAGAAUCGAAGUUGUCACAACUCUCAAUUAUUUUUUAAAUACUGCAUAGAUUGAGUUUUGGUUUAUUACUAACCCUUCCCAAAAUUGCAUCGGAUCUAAAACUACUAGAUCUCAUCCCAUUCCCAUGUAAAUUACCACAGACCGCAGUACCGGGGCUGGAGCGGAGUGAAGCUGUCUGCUGUAAGAGGAGUGGCCAUGUGAGGGCAUGGAGUCAUUAGUCUCACAAACACACUUUGGACUGAAGAGGAUCAUUUCUUUUUGUUCGUGAGGUCACUGUCCGGGCCUCUCAUAUCACGACCAGACGGCGGGUCUCCAUCUUCUUUGACUCCUGUGGCCCUCGCUGCUUUACACAAUCUGUUCUAUAAGGUUCAGGUGUUUUCAAGUUGGAAAGAUCAUAAAUACUCAAAAUUGUUUUCAAGUUAGCAAAUUCUUUUAACAGUCUUUUAUGCAAAAAUUGAAUUAAUAAAAUAAUAUUUUGUAAAGA